ACCGGUCCCGCCUCCCUUGACGCCCCGCCCCGCCCCUCCUCCCUGCUCUCUUAGAAAGAGCCAAUCGCUCCGUCUCAUUGGCGGCCCCGACUCGUCCAGCUGGGUCGCGUUAGAGUGCCCGCCCCACUCCUCCCAGCCACAGCCCCGCCCCACCUCCCCCAGGCCAAUCAGUUUGGUUCCUCUCCCCUAAGCCACGCCCCCGCUACCUCGCUCCUCCUCCCACCCAAUCCCGUCGGUCUCUCCCCCCGUGUCCCCGCCCCUGCGUCCCCGCCCCUCCCGCCCCGCCCCCCGUCCAAUGCUGAGCUCAGUCUGCGUCUCGUCCUUCCGCGGGCGCCAGGGGGCCAGCAAGCAGCAGCCGGCGCCACCGCCGCAGCCGCCCGAGUCCCCGCCGCCGCCACCGCUGCCGCCGCAGCAGCAGCAGCCUGCGCAGCCCGGCCCCGCCGCGUCCCCGGCGGGCCCCCCGGCACCCCGCGGGCCCGGGGACCGGCGCGCCGAGCCAUGCCCCGGGCUGCCGGCGGCGGCCAUGGGGCGGCACGGCGGCGGCGGUGGCGACAGCGGCAAGAUCGUGAUCAACGUGGGCGGCGUGCGCCAUGAGACGUACCGCUCGACGCUGCGCACCCUGCCGGGGACGCGGCUGGCCGGCCUGACGGAGCCCGAGGCGGCGGCACGCUUCGACUACGACCCGGGCGCCGACGAGUUCUUCUUUGACCGGCACCCGGGAGUCUUCGCGUACGUGCUCAACUACUACCGCACCGGCAAGCUGCACUGCCCAGCCGACGUGUGCGGGCCCCUGUUUGAGGAGGAGCUCGGCUUCUGGGGCAUCGACGAGACCGACGUGGAGGCCUGCUGCUGGAUGACCUACCGGCAGCAUCGCGACGCUGAGGAGGCGCUCGACUCCUUCGAGGCGCCCGACCCCGCGGGCGCCGCCAACGCCGCCAACGCCGCAGGCGCCCACGACGGAGGCCUGGACGACGAGGCGGGCGCGGGCGGCGGCGGCCUGGACGGAGCGGGCGGCGAGCUCAAGCGCCUCUGCUUCCAGGACGCGGGCGGCGGCGCCGGGGGGCCGCCAGGGGGCGCGGGCGGCGCGGGCGGCACAUGGUGGCGCCGCUGGCAGCCCCGCGUGUGGGCGCUCUUCGAGGACCCCUACUCGUCGCGGGCUGCCAGGUAUGUGGCCUUCGCCUCCCUCUUCUUCAUCCUCAUCUCCAUCACCACCUUCUGCCUGGAAACCCAUGAGGGCUUCAUCCAUAUUAGCAACAAGACGGUGACCCAGGCCUCCCCGAUCCCCGGGGCACCUCCGGAGAACAUCACCAACGUGGAGGUGGAGACGGAGCCCUUCCUGACCUACGUGGAGGGGGUGUGCGUGGUCUGGUUCACCUUCGAGUUCCUCAUGCGCAUCACCUUCUGCCCAGACAAGGUGGAGUUUCUUAAAAGCAGCCUCAACAUCAUCGACUGUGUGGCCAUCCUGCCCUUCUAUCUCGAGGUGGGCCUCUCGGGCCUCAGCUCCAAGGCCGCCAAAGACGUGCUGGGCUUCCUGCGGGUGGUCCGCUUCGUCCGCAUCCUGCGCAUCUUCAAGCUGACCCGGCACUUCGUGGGGCUGCGCGUGCUGGGACACACGCUCCGCGCCAGCACCAACGAGUUCCUGCUGCUCAUCAUCUUCCUGGCCCUGGGGGUGCUCAUCUUCGCCACCAUGAUUUACUACGCUGAGCGCAUUGGCGCCGACCCCGAUGACAUCCUGGGCUCCAACCACACCUACUUCAAGAACAUCCCCAUUGGCUUCUGGUGGGCUGUGGUCACCAUGACGACCCUGGGCUAUGGAGACAUGUACCCCAAGACGUGGUCGGGGAUGCUGGUCGGGGCGCUGUGUGCCCUGGCGGGGGUGCUGACCAUCGCCAUGCCUGUGCCCGUCAUUGUCAACAACUUUGGCAUGUACUAUUCGCUGGCCAUGGCCAAGCAGAAGCUGCCCAAGAAGAAGAACAAACACAUCCCCCGGCCCCCGCAACCGGGCUCGCCCAACUACUGCAAGCCUGACCCACCCCCGCCACCCCCGCCCCACCCGCACCACGGCAGCGGGGGCAUCAGCCCGCCGCCACCCAUCACCCCACCCUCCAUGGGGGUGACUGUGGCCGGGGCCUACCCAGCGGGGCCCCACACGCACCCCGGGCUGCUCAGGGGGGGAGCGGGUGGGCUGGGGAUCAUGGGGCUGCCUCCUCUGCCAGCCCCCGGCGAGCCUUGCCCGUUGGCUCAGGAGGAGGUGAUUGAGAUCAACCGGGCAGAUCCUCGCCCCAAUGGGGAUCCGGCAGCAGCUGCGCUUGCCCACGAGGACUGCCCAGCCAUUGACCAGCCUGCCAUGUCCCCGGAAGACAAGAGCCCCAUCACGCCUGGAAGCCGUGGCCGCUAUAGCCGGGACCGAGCCUGCUUCCUCCUCACCGACUAUGCCCCUUCCCCUGAUGGCUCCAUCCGAAAAGCCACUGGUGCUCCCCCACUGCCCCCCCAAGACUGGCGUAAGCCAGGCCCCCCAAGCUUCUUGCCCGACCUCAACGCCAACGCCGCGGCCUGGAUAUCCCCCUAGUGGACGAACCCCCUCCCCCCGGGCUCUUGUCACCGCCUGAGACCUCGCGAGACUUUCGGUCCCCCCCGCCCCUUCCCCCCAGGUUAGCAAUUGGGAAUGGCUGGGAGGGGGUGUCCCCAAGACACUGGGCUUCAAAUCUCCCCCCAAGCCCUCCCUCCUACGAUCAAGACACCUUUUGUCCAGACAGCUCCCUUAGCGUUGCCUGGAAAAGCCACAGAGCUCCCUGCGGGGGUGCAGAACCCUGCAGGCAGCCCCAGGCUUUGCAGAAACCACACACACUGUUGCUGGAUCUUGAGUCCCAUUAGCUGUGAGAUGCCUGUGAGAGCCUUCCCGCACCCGUCAGAAGCUCAGAGCCUUCUUGGACCCUUUAAAGAUGUCCCUCUCCCCAGCCCUCCGCCUCACCGCCCCCCACCCCCGACCCCGUCCUUAGAAUCUUCUGGAGGAGCCUCCCUCCCCCCCCACCCCCCCCCACUGCUCCUGGAGUUCUCAUCGGAUUCCCCAAGGGCACUGCCAGCUUCGCUCCACUCAGCCCCCUUGCAGACCCCACCCCCUGCCUGCUCUCUUUCCCUACAACUAGGUCAGCCCCCAGCCCCGCUACGGCGGCCGCACCGUUCCCUGCCCUCUCCGCUGGCUGCUCCCACAUGCAUUCCACCCAGCCCCUCCCCACGCCCCUGCCGCCCACCAUCCCGCCUUGCUGCCCCCCACCUUUUGCCUCAGGUGAGGGGACCAGUGGAGGGGGGGAAGGGCGGUGGACUGUGGUGGGAAUGGGGCGGGGGAGGCUCGGUGGGCACCAACCUGCCUCCUAAUCCGGAGUCUCUCCCCCCUCCCCGAUGUCUCCCCCUUUCUCAUCGAUGUUGACUGACUCCCCGAUUUGUUCACUUUCUCUCUCCAUCUCCUUGGUCCAUCUCUGUCCAUCUGUCUCUUGUCAUCCGUCCUUUUGUGUCUCUGUCUGCCUGACUCUGUCUGUCUUGCCUUCUCUGUCUCUCUGGGUAUCUGUUGUCCUCCCCUUCCAUUUCUUUCUCUCUCUGUCUCUUUCUCCCUGCCUUGGGUCUCUCUGUCUGACCCUUCCCUGCACCCCAUCUUCGUGCUUCCCCCCUGUGUCUGCACACCUCCCCACCCCCCAGGUUACGAGAAAUCCCGCAGCCUCAGCAGCAUCGCGGGCCUGAGCGGGGUGUCCCUGCGCCUCGCGCCCCUUGCCACCCCCCCUGGCUCUCCCCGGGCCGCCCGCCGCGCUCCCCCGACCCUGCCCUCCAUCCUUUAGCGCUCCCCUCCCCCCUGUGGGGGGACUCGGGGGUGACCGGGAAGAAGGUCAAAGGAGCUGGGGGUGGGGGGUGGGGAAAAGGGUUUUUUUAAAAAAAAUCAAAAAGUCAUUAAUAAUAUGCAACCGAGAUGACGAUGCCAGCAGACACCCCCGGGCCCCUCACCCCCAACCUGGGCCCCCAGGAUGGAGAGAGGGGCCACAGCCCGUCCCCCCAACUCUUCCCUCCCCAAAAAAAGCCUUCUCAGGUCUCCACGAGCCAUAGGACAUCCCCCUGCCAUCAACUUGUGUAAAUAAGUCCAAAUUAUGCCAGUUACAUCUUGGGGCACCUCCCCCCACACACUGCAUGCCUUCCCUAACCUGGAGCCCCCACUCCAAGUCCACCUCAGCAAUAAGCCGCCAGGGGCCGCAUGCGCGGGUUUGAGGGGCAGGCACUCUGGGAAGGGGGUGGCACCUCCCGGGGGUCGGGCUGGCCUUUAAGGUCUCCAGCCUUCCCAUCCUUCACCCCAGGAGGACAACCAACCCUGUGCGUUGAUUAGGAGAAAACAAACCAGAAACUAGAAACAGUGUAGGGGAAGGAGGAACAGUUACCCAAGCCCCAGAUCGGAGUUGAGCUCAGGUGGCGGGAGGGCGGGGCCGAGUUGAGCUCAGGUGGUGGGAGGGCGGGGCGGGCUUUGGACCUGCUCCCUCAGCCUUUAGGAGAAUUCCUCUGGUGAAUUUCACCCUCUCAUCCGCCCCUUCCCCCAGGGACCUGCUCGCCUCUAUUCUUGCUGCAUGGACUCAGACCUCCUAUCCCAGAAUUCCUGGGAUGAUCUGGCCCUAGCACACGAAAUUCCCCGACUAUCUCCCUCCAUUCCCAGGACAUGAGACCUGCACCCAGAAUUCUGAGACUGACCCUGGCACGCCACAUCUCCCAAUCCCCACACACUCCUGCGACUUAACCUCUGCACACAGAGGCUCCCUGAACCACCCUCCCUCCCCACUCCUGCCACCCCAAACACCCCCACCAAAUUCCCUGAACUGCGUCCCAGCACUUCUCAAACCUCCAAGACUUGACCCAGCUCUUUUCAGCUCAAAUUCAGCCUUUGGGAUGCUCCAAAUCCUUCCCACAACUGACAUUUCUUGGACACCCCCAAAGCCUCAGGCCUGUUCCGCACCCAUAUCCCCAAAGCCCUAACAGACUUGUCCAGCCCAGGUUCCCUUGAUGCUAGAACUUCCAAGAUAGGCGCAACCUGUCUGCAAUUCCAGGGAACCAGACCCUCCCCAAGCACCCUCUUUGUCUUACGCCUAACCCUGAGUCUCUUCCCUGAGAUGGUGCCCCAAAGGUACCCUCUUCACAGACACCAGUGUUUCCCAGAGGGUUGUAUUUGUACCUUUGGUGGUGUGCUAAGGUUUGAGGCAGUAUGAGGACAAACACUUGUUUUAAAAGUUUUGUCUCUAAUACGCAUUUUGUACAGAAGCCGAUAAGUGCAGGCAUCGCUGCUUGGCUAGGACACGGUUUAUUUAGGUUAAGAGUGUUUCCAUUUAAAGUAGUCCACAGAUGAUCACAGAGGCUGUUCCCGAAGGGAGGAACACUGGAGUAUCAGAAGAUUGGGAACCGACAACACCCAGCUCGGCUGGGAUCCCAGCCCCCCUUCCCCAGCGGUCCUCACCGCGUCACGCUCGCGGGUGGAAAAUCAUUUCCCACCUCCUAUCCUGGCUCAAGGAUGCGCUACCUCCCCCAAGCCCAGAGACCACACCGGUCCCAGACUCUUUAGCGGACCCCCCUUUUGGAGCCGGGGUCCCACGGAAUUAGCCACCUCCCUCCCUCUGCUCCCACGGCCUCAGGAACCCCCCACCCGAGGGUGGAUGGGGGGCGUCACUGAGCACGAUUCUCGAUGCAACGAUUCCUAUGCAAGGGGCAUUUUGAGUCCCCCCCAUCCUUCCCUCGGACCCUAAACCCUGGUGAAGCAGGGGUGAGGGGUGGGGCGGGUUUUGGUGGGGGCGGGGCAAAGGGCUAGGGGCUCCAGACACCAGGGUACGGGGUGGGGACUGAUUAUAUUGCCAAAGGGUUCAACUUCUUUAACAAGCCCCCCCGUUUCCCCUGACCUUCACGAAAGCCGAAGGAGGCGGGGAAAGGGGGUGAGGGUCUUUUCCAAAGGGUACUGACCUCUUCCCAACGUCUCCCCCUGCUCGCCAGUCCGCCACACGUACCCAGCUUUUGAGUUCAGCUUUUCAAAAUAACCACAAUCAUGAUAAACUUCUACAAAACGUGAUUCUCCUCCCCUCCCACCCCAUCCCCCAAGUCAAUAGUGUGGGAUUCGGGGAGGGAGAGAGCGAGCUAAAGGGACUCUUUCCAAGUCCGGCUCCCCCUUUUCCCCCCGGCCGCCAGGGUGCCUGCACCUACACGCAUGCGCUGCAUGACGCGCCCCCCACACGCAUGUCGCACCCCUCCUGCGCUCCGGGAACGCACGGACACGGGCCAGGGGGCGGGGCGAUUGGGGAGGAAUGAAUGGCGGGGGGUCUUCCUGAGCUCCGCGGCUCACCCUCCCCAACACACACACACACACACACAGAGCAAUAAGUUUCUCUCACUCAAAUGUGGGCGGGGCGGGCCUAGCCUGUCGCUGGUGGGGGGAGUGGUGAGGGGGCGCUCUCAGGGAUGGGGGCGGGGUUCGGAGACAGUGUGGGGAGGGGAGGUCUGCAAAUCGUCCAACUCUGGUGCUAAUGGCGGGUCUUCUCAGCCCACCCGCAGGGCAGGGAGGGAGGGGUCGGCGUGGCCCCUUCCCCAAGCCUCCCCCACGCCCACCCUGGGUGCAUGAACCGCCCAAUGCAGAAGCUGCCGCAUGUCACCCCCCUCUCCCCAAAGAAAAAGUGUCAUGCCCCCUUCCCACCCACCCUCACUCCCCACCAAAAUAAACGUUUCCUUUUCAUUUAAAAA